GACAGAGAGUAUGGGGAGCCGGUAUUUGGGCGCGGAGCUAGGCGGGGUGGACUUUGGGACAUAGACGGGGAACCGGGUCCUGGAGCCGGGAGUAGUGCCAGCGCCCCGGAACCACGCCCCCUGUUACCCCGCCCCUCGCAUUUCGUUUUAGACCUCUCCCAGUCCUUCGGGACUCGGUCUGGUUUAUACUAGGUCGUGCUAGGGGCAGCGUGACCAGCCAGGGCGGAGAGAGGAUGCUUAACUCCUUAGGCUCGAACUCCUCCCUUCCUACCCACCUCUCUCCCUUCUCGUUCGGACAGGUGAAGAAACAAGAAAACUAAGAAAUCCGAGCGGUUGGAGGGGGAGUCUGUGUGGAUGGGAUGGGGACGCCGGGGGAGGGGCUGGGCCGCUGCUCCCAUGCCCUGAUCCGGGGAGUCCCAGAGAGCCUGGCGUCGGGGGAAGGUGCGGGGGCUGGCCUUCCCGCUCUGGAUCUGGCCAAAGCUCAAAGGGAGCACGGGGUGCUGGGAGGUAAACUGAGGCAACGACUGGGGCUACAGCUGCUAGAACUGCCACCUGAGGAGUCAUUGCCGCUGGGACCGCUGCUUGGCGACACGGCCGUGAUCCAAGGGGACACGGCCCUAAUCACGCGGCCCUGGAGCCCCGCUCGUAGGCCAGAGGUCGAUGGAGUCCGCAAAGCCCUGCAAGACCUGGGGCUCCGAAUUGUGGAAAUAGGAGACGAGAACGCGACGCUGGAUGGCACUGACGUUCUCUUCACCGGCCGGGAGUUUUUCGUAGGCCUCUCCAAAUGGACCAAUCACCGAGGAGCUGAGAUCGUGGCGGACACGUUCCGGGACUUCGCCGUCUCCACUGUGCCAGUCUCGGGUCCCUCCCACCUGCGCGGUCUCUGCGGCAUGGGGGGACCUCGCACUGUUGUGGCAGGCAGCAGCGACGCUGCCCAAAAGGCUGUCCGGGCAAUGGCAGUGCUGACAGAUCACCCAUAUGCCUCCCUGACCCUCCCAGAUGACGCAGCUGCUGACUGUCUCUUUCUUCGUCCUGGGUUGCCUGGUGUGCCCCCUUUCCUCCUGCACCGUGGAGGUGGGGAUCUGCCCAACAGCCAGGAGGCACUGCAGAAGCUCUCUGAUGUCACCCUGGUACCUGUGUCCUGCUCAGAACUGGAGAAGGCUGGCGCCGGGCUCAGCUCCCUCUGCUUGGUGCUCAGCACACGCCCCCACAGCUGAGGGCCUGGCCUUGGGGUACUGCUGGCCAGGGGUAGGAUAGUAUAGGAAGUAGAAGGGGAAGGAGGGUUAGAUAGAGAAUGCUGAAUAGGCAGUAGUUGGGAGAGAGCCUCAAUAUUGGGGGAGGGGAGAGUGUAGGGAAAAGGAUCCACUGGGUGAAUCCUCCCUCUCAGAACCAAUAAAAUAGAAUUGACCUUUUA